GCUGGGAGUCCUGGUGCCGCCGGCUGCACUUCUGUGUGUCUUUCAGGAAGCCACAGGGCAGGGGGCGUCUGUGCAGAGAAGCGGGGGAGUGAGUAGCAGGCAGGCCCAGCUUGUGUACCAGCCCAGUGACAUAUAUAGAAACAUAAAUCAGGCUAGAGCCGGCGCGCCCGGGCGCGCACCUGUGUAUGGACCCGCAGGCAUGUCUGUACACUGGGUGGGCACCUGUCUUGUGAGUGGCUCCGGGUGUGGCUGCUCCUCGGACUUUCAGUUUAUGUAAGAUUUAUCUCUAGGGGCCUACCUUCCCCCAUCUCCAGAGGGGAACAUAAGAAGUUUAACGGAGCUGGGACUGAGCAGAUUAAGGGAGUGGAGCGGAGGCUGGGCCGGAGAGAGUGGGGACUGUGAGUGCUAGUGGGUAAGGAUCCAUCUGUUUGCCCCGUCCCCCAGCCAGAAAGGCAUUUUGGAAAGACUGGCGUGGCAAGCGUCGCCCUGAAACGUCCACAGAGCCCAAGAAGUGAUGAUCACUGAGUGAGUGGCACUGGGCUGAGACUGGCCAGUUUGUUAACAACAGGGAUGCUAGCAGUUAGGAAGGCCAGGAGGAAACUCAGGAUGGGGACCAUCUGCUCCCCCAACCCCAGCGGGACAAAGACAUCAUCGGAGGUCUGCAAUGCCGACUGGAUGGCCUCGCUCCCCCCUCACCUCCACAACCUCCCCCUUUCCAAUCUGGCAAUCCCAGGCUCACAUGAUUCAUUCAGCUACUGGGUGGAUGAAAAGUCCCCAGUGGGGCCUGACCAAACCCAAGCUAUCAAACGCCUCGCCAGGAUCUCCUUGGUGAAGAAGCUAAUGAAGAAGUGGUCUGUGACUCAGAACCUGACAUUUCGAGAACAGCUGGAAGCUGGGAUCCGCUACUUUGACCUGCGUGUGUCUUCCAAACCAGGGGAUGCCGACCAGGAGAUCUACUUCAUCCAUGGGCUUUUUGGCAUCAAGGUCUGGGAUGGGCUGAUGGAAAUUGACUCGUUUCUUACACAGCACCCCCAGGAGAUUAUCUUCCUGGAUUUCAACCACUUCUAUGCCAUGGAUGAGACCCAUCACAAAUGCCUGGUUCUGCGGAUCCAGGAGGCCUUUGGAAACAAGCUGUGCCCAGCCUGCAGUGUGGAAAGUUUGACGCUGCGAACUCUGUGGGAGAAGAACUGCCAGGUUCUUAUUUUCUACCACUGUCCCUUCUACAAGCAGUACCCCUUCCUGUGGCCAGGAAAGAAGAUUCCAGCGCCCUGGGCAAACACCACAAGUGUGCGCAAACUAAUCCUCUUCUUGGAGACCACUCUGAGUGAGCGGGCCUCACGGGGCUCCUUCCAUGUCUCCCAAGCGAUCCUCACCCCCAGAGUGAAGACCAUUGCCCGGGGCUUGGUUGGGGGCCUCAAGAACACGCUGGUUCAUAGGAAUCUUCCUGCCAUCCUGGACUGGGUGAAAACUCAGAAGCCUGGAGCCAUGGGUGUCAACAUCAUCACAUCUGACUUCGUGGACCUGGUGGACUUUGCUGCGACUGUCAUCAAGUUGAAUGACCUCCUACAGGAGGACACAGCUCUGGCUAAAUGCUGAUUUAAUUUUUAAUUUAACCUUAAUGUUGAAUUUGUUGAUCCAGGGUAGAGUUCUAAAGGAUGUCCUGUUAGGAUGGCCCCUGGGGCAGUGAUGAUGAAGUAAGAGGAAGAUGGCUUUUUUUUCUCCCUUCCUCACAGGGCCAUUUAGAUAAAAUUACAGGGCUAUUAAUUGCAUUUUUCCCAAAUGAGACUUUUUUUAAAACUUAAGUCCAAGGGAAGAAAGCACGCUUCAUGUGACCAAGGUCAGGACCUCCCCAGUGGCUUAUGGUGGUGAAUGGAAUUUGGAAAUAGGAUCUCUAGGACCCAUUGGGGUAUUGAGUGUCCCCCUAAUUGGCCCAGCUCCCUAUUGUCGUCUGGGGUGUUGUGUUUGAGCCGGUGAAAAAGUUGAACCAGAAACACAUUCCUGGUGAAAAAGACUGGCUCAUUGCAGCUGUGGACCACCAUCUGGGGUGGAUCUAACAUCAACCAGGGGCUCUGAGGGGGAAAAGAGCCAAGCACCAGGUCUCUCUAGGAUUGUUGGAUGUCACCACUUUUCUGAGAGAGUAGGACUCAUUUAUCACUAAGAUGUUUCAAACACAAGCUGUUCUUUCAUAGCGUAUACUGGUAACUGGUCACCUCAUUCUUCAGAUAAACAGUGCAUACUACCCUUAGUAUCAGAAACAUGCUUCCCAGUUUUAAAACUUGGAUUCCUUUCUAUUUCUUUUGGCCCCUUCUUAAAAGUGAAAAGAACAAUGAUGGGAGAUCUUUUUAGCGUGGGGCCCAACAAGAGAUAGAUAUGCAUGUUUGCUGCAUGCCAGAUAUCUUUUAUUUAAUUCUACAGCUUUUUCCAGAAUGGCUGCCAGGUAGAGCACCUGCAUCAUUUUGGCAAAGUCCUCUUUGGAGUGGGGUCUUCAAGCCUGAUCUUGGAAUUGCGUUUUAUUAUUGUCUGCCUAGGACUCAGGUCUGCACUGUGGGACACAACGCUAAGUGGAAGGCCCCUUAUCCAUGGCACCAUGGAAGCAGGCGCAGGAUGCAUGGGAAACUGCAAUGGCAUUAAAGGAGGAAGCUCCAAGUGGAUUUGGAGCCAUUCUAUAACUCCUUGAAAACAAGACUACCUCGGGGAUAUUUAGGAUGACUCGUGUGUCACCAAGUGAGAAAUACCUAGUGUUGGAACAUUUCCAGUCCUUCUCUUGAUGGUUCUACUUUCUGCAGGUUGUUUUGAGCCUACCAAUCACUACUGCAUGAGGACUUUGAAACUCGAGAGGGAAUUUUUUUUUUAUCGAUAAGAGGUGCUUAUCUAUAAGGAGCCCUCUUGUGUUUUGAUUUAUUUAUUUAUUUAUUUAUUUAUUUAUUUAUAGAUUAAAUAUCUGCCGUGCUUCUUACAUCAAGAGCACUCACACAGGAGCUUACUGAACUUUUCUUACCCAGGAUAGAUGCUGCUAUGGUCUUUCUGUCCUGAACAGGACCACGCAUCUCAGGGCUGUGAGUGAUUCCUGACUCUGCUGUUCAUGUCCUGGCUCCCCCAGUCCUCCUGGGGACAGUAUACAUGUGUGGAUGUGGUCUAGAUCUGAGAAGUCACUACCAAGCCAUGCCCAUGAACGAAGAUAAAAUGGGUCGUGAAGAACUAUUAGUUCAUAAGUAGACCCUCCAGAAGAGUGUUGAAAAGAAAGGCUCUAGAAAGAAAACUAGGCAUGGAAAUGUGUGCACUUUGUUGCUCCUCAGCACCAUCUGAGAAUCCCUAAGGAAGUGGCAGCUUCUGGAUUCUUAAGAAGGAAAUAUAAACAUGGAGUCCCGAAUGGAUGUAUGCAUUUAUAAAGAUUGUCAGACUCUUCUUCCAGCAGUUUCCUGUUUCUGUCUUUUGAUGCCCAUAGAUGGAUUUUGCAUGUUGCUUGCAGAGAGGGGUGUCCUAGGUGAGGUACUAAAAGCACAUCCACACCCCCAACUCUUGGUCUUCCACCCUAUACGUUCUGUAAAACAAUUUAAGACCUGGCUUUUAGCUUGCACCCUUGAGGAGGUCAUAAUAGAAAUGCCUCUGGGAAAAUCUGGUUGAACUUUCCUUUUUUUGCAUUUGAACCCCUCCCCAAAGGGUUUUCUGGGAUAAUGUCAAAUUCUGUAGGGCCUUCUCUGGAUAAGAGUAAGUAAGUGUGUUCCCUCGUUUUCUAAACUUUCCUUCAAUUCUGAUGCUAAAUGCUAAUGACAAGCUCUGAAAUCCCUGGUCUACCCUCAGGGUUUUAUUUUUGUUGUCAUUUCAUUUUGCUUUUGUUUUUAAUUUUUGGUCAAUUGCUAGGGGCUAGAUCAUUUCCCCACUUUUUACCCUUUGUUACUUGGCAAAGAGAUAAGGAGGCAAGAGGAGAAUUACUGUUCUCUGUUUUAUUUGAGCCUCGGCUUUGUCCAGGUGUUUGGUGCUAUGAGGCCAGGUGUGUUGACAAGUAUCUACACAGGAUGCCAGUAACACCCAAGGGCUGCUGACUGUUCCAUGAAAUGUUUACAUGAUUUUGUCCUUUAGUUCUUAAAUAUAUGGUUGCACUUCACUUGGGUUGUAACAUUUAAGUGCACCUCAGUGUUUGCAUGAUAAAUGUCAUCAAGCAUGACACAAAAGCCCAGAAAACUGUACCAAGGUUGCAUGCACGGAGUCCUGCUCUGCGUGGUGCGUGCAGGUGCUCACUCCUCCAUGCUGCUUGGAGCUGCCAGCCUUGCUUGCAAUUUGAAAGUCUGCACAAGAGUUCUGGGAGAUAGGAGGAUUAUUUACAAUUUUCCCUUGAUAAACACCUUUGCAUCAGCAGAAUCUCUGCCUCAAGAAAAAGUUGCUUAACAUAUUGUAAAGGAUGUGUGCCUUCUGCUCCUUGACCGUGAGACCAGACAGGAGAACUCAGGCAUGUGGGACAGAGGGAAAACAGAUUUUAGGUUCAUGACUCAUUCUGCAACUGCCAACAAUAAAAUAGUGACCCAACCACAUCACUUAUUCUCACAAGUUCUGGAGACCUUUCAGAUCAAAACAAGGCUCUCAUACUUGCUCAGAACUAACUUCAAGAUCAGCUAAGAAGCUACUUGAUUGAGCCAAAGAGGACUUUAGUUUCACAGAAUUUUAGGUCAUAUUUAUUCUGAAAUACAACUGAGCUAUUCAUGAGCUCCCUGGACCAUUUCCCACACAGCCAUAUUUCCAUGGCUUUGUGGCAAAGGGGACCAUCAAAGGUUUUAGUUCGGUUAGAGUAGUGUUUACAGGCUUGAACUUUGAGCCUUUUAGAGAGACCACCAGGAUUUCAUGGAUACAGAAGGAUUGGAGAGAGAGGUCGAGAUGGACUUAAUGGAAGGGAAUAAGUUAUUGAACAUUAAAUUUUAAAUUAGUGGCAGACCUCCAAGAGAGUCAUGCCAAAAAAGUUUUUAUAUUUGCUGUAUUAAACUCAAUGGUAAUUACUUUUAGUCAUUUUCCUUAGCACUGAAUCUAAACCCUGAAUUACCGAGAGCAGUUAAGCCACAGUCCCAGGAUUUUAUUAUAAACUCAAAGAAAAGCACAAAAUCUGAGCCCAGGUAAUGAUCCAUCUUAGGAAUCCUAGUUCUUUUUACAUGAUCUCAUAUUCAUCCAAAAAAAUUGUUUCUUCUCAAUAAGACAACGUAGUAGAGUAUUCUGGAAUUAAAUGCAGUUUUAUGGCGUGGCGGGACUUUCCAUCUCUCGUUUUGAGAAUCUUGCCAUGAGAAAGUGCUUCCCAAUGAGACAUUACUACCUCCCAGCUAGGAGGCUUAGCACAAUGCUAAAGGUGGAGCAACAGAAGAAAUUCAGAUGGAAAUGAAACUACUUCUUCCUGGGAAGUAAAAGAGCUACAUGAAACCAGUCCAUCCUGCAGAUUUAGUUCAUGCCACAGUUGAAGUUUGUGUGAUGUUUCUUAGUAGCUAAUUUCAAAUUUUUACUGUUAGAUUCUAAGAAACAGAGUGGGCUAAUGAUUGGAGCACAGCCAUGAGACUCCGCUCCGUUAGCUGAGCAUGUGAUCCUGUGCUAAAUCUUUCUUGGUUCCUUCAUCUUUGAAGAUGCUGUCUGCUACUUUAGUGCUGACUGAUUUGCAAAUCUUGGUUGAUUAGCUCCCCAAUCAUAAGGUCCCUAAUGAUUAGAUUAAAUGCCUUAUACUCAGGGGGUGUGCAGAUAUGCUAUUCUUCCUUCUGUGGCUUGGGUGGAAAAGCUGCUUGGGCUUAUUUCCCAACAGUGUGAUGUAGGAUGGCAGAACUUAUCUAGGAAUGGCACCUUUGAUGAUCCAUAUAAUGAAAUGUGUAGAGCUCAAAGAAAUCUGCCAACAUGUAUGUGGACUCUUGAGAGGUGGGCUUUCCCAGUACAUGCUAAACAGACUUGUUAUGCCAAGAGGAAGUGAAUAGAAAUGAUAGCAUCAAAUAUCCAAACUGACAGGAAGUUUCUUUUGCAUAGCAUAGAACAUGGUUGUCUUCUGAGUUCCACUAAUGUUCCAGGAUAUCUUGGCCCUCUGCCUCUGGCUGCUCCCUGGUGUUUGGCACCAUAGCGUUGUCACUUACAACCAUUGCCUUGGGACACACAGAGUGAACUGUUUGAGUGAUAAGUAAUUUAGGUAGAAACUUUACCCUUAAUUUCAAAUGAUACCAAACAGCUCAUUACUACCCCAAGGGACGCUCUCCGUAGCUUCUGGAUUCCCCAGUUUCCUUCUAGAAACAAGGACUCCAAUAGCACUAUAACCCUAAACAGGCCCUAACCCAGAAGAAUACACCACAAAAUGCGAUUGAUUUUCUCAAAAUAUCACAGUCUUAGACACUAUACAAAUAAUUCAAGAAAAUUCUUUCUACCCUGCAGUGGAUAUAGUAUUCUAUUAUAUUCUCCAGCAAAACUUUUAGGACUUUUCAAACUCAUUUCUAAGCCAAAUAGUUUAGAUAAAUAUUUACCCUUAUAUUUGGGGGGAAUUCAGGCUCACCAUUUGCCGAGGCAAGCCCAUCAACAGUCUAGAGGCAUAUUCUGUGUCAUUCCUUCCCGUCUCCUUCAUAGAAUACUACUUUUUCCUUUUGUCUCCUGGCCAUUCUCCAUCAUCUGCUGAUUAUUGCUAACCACAGGAUGCUGGCAAAGCUUACAGUGAUAGGCACGUGUGUUCAGUGAUGUCCAAUACACUCUUAUCACAGUGGUUAUUGCUUCUUACUCUUUUCAAAUGCAUUAUUCUACCCCUCAACCUACAUCCAAUCAUUAGAACUAUACUGGAGCCCAGAACUUGGGACCAAUACUUAAUUCAAAUAGCAGGGGCUUGCUCACAAACAUUAAGCCCAACAAGAAGCACAGCACUUUGAAAAGUCAAAUAGGCCUUUGGUAGCUCUGUACAUUUGCAGUUUUACAUUUGUUAUUAGUUUAUAGCACUAAUAACACUUCAGUCGUGAAUCUACAGUCUCAAUAUGAUAAGUCUUAGAACAUGUUCUAGAAAUAGUGGUACCUUGCUGCUAUUAUACUUAGUAACUUAUACCCCAAUAUAAUAAUAAGUAUUAAAUACAGAUUGUGUAUGCAUUCUUUGUGUGUAUAUGCCAACUGUACUACUUAACCUCACUGAUGAGCAAUUAGAAAAAUACAGAAAUUGUCAUAGUGAAAAUAAGUCUUGGUCAAUUCAGAUGAUACGUGAACCUGAUAAAUGCUCUAAUAGAUAUGCUAUUUUGUCCUGUAUUGCUUGUUUUACAGUAUGGUGCAUGUUGUUUGCUAAGUAAAAUGAUAAUAAUAAUAAAGUAUACCAAUUUUAAGGUUAGAAUUAAAAUUUUGCACAUAUGCUUCUUGAUAUUCUGAAAUGUAUUCUGUGGCUUAAUUAUCUUAUUCAUACACAUUUCACUUGGCUUUUUACCCCUAGGAAAUAAUUGUCCAAGUAUAUAUCUCGUCUUCUUUCUUGUAACUUUGAUUAAACUGCUUACUUCAACUUACAACAUUGUAAAGCCAGAAUACCUCAUUUUAACAGUGAAAAAAAAUAUGAUGACCUGAUGUGUUCUCUUGUAUUUGAUUUGAACUACCUAAAUAGGCUUAACUGUAAUAAUAAAUAUACAAUUUUGGCAGGCAUUUUUUCCUUUGUUUGGAUGAACAUUUUGUUAUUGGUCCACUUCUAAUUUUGUCUUAAAGAGUUAUAAACUCAGUGUCAAUAAAACAUCUUGUUAUAUAAUAUUGGACAAAAA